AGUGUGCUGGGCAGGGGGAGGAAAGGCGAGGAUUCGGGACGGGCCCAGCCUCGUCAGAACAAACCCCUUCUCGCUGCCUUUUCAUGGAGCCCUGGCACUCCGGUUUCCGGGCGUUCUGCCCCAGGGCUGAGACUUGGAUUUGUGGCUCCUGCAGCAUCCCUGAGGGAGCAUGAUUUGGAGAGGGCCUUGGGCAUGGAGCAGGACCAAGGAACGGCCACAGGGCAUAUCUUACAGCUCCUUUAACGUCAGGCCUCCAGAACCCUCUGUUCUCUAAACCAUCCAGGGCCCCACAGUCUUGGGAAAAAUUUGGGGGUUGGACAUAGGAUAUCCUGUGAGGAAGUUCUGGGCCAGGGACUGGAAGCCCAGUGUCCUGGCUUCAGGUUUGCCCCUGGCUGGGCGUGUACCGUUCAGCCCUAUUUGGGAGCCUGGUUGCCACACCUAGAGGUUCCUGCUCUGCUGACUUCACAGGAAGUUGCUUGGCUCUGGUAACCAGAUGGCCGGGUGGAGGGGUGCCUGGGGCUUCCACUCCUGAACAGAGAGCUUAACUGUCCUAGAGUUCAUGGGGAGCCACCUAGCCACACUGGAGCCCUUCAGAGCUCACCCUGGCUGCUGGGUGGAGAAAGGCCUAUAGAUGUCACAGGUGGAUCCUGGGAGGCCAGGAAGGAGGACUUGGAGCCAUCCACUAGCCUAGACUGGGCUGGUUGCAGUGACAGUACAGGGAGAAGUAUAGAAGAAUGGGCAUUGUCCAAGGAUCCUGAAACUCCGCCACAUCUGGAACCUGAAGUUGAUGCGUUGGUGAGGAGGAAUGGGCCCCUCGAAGUGGGCCGGGCCGGCCCCACCUGCCUCUGCCCAGAUUUGCCCUCCUCCUGCUCUGCCCAGGAGGACCCCUGCAGCUGCAGACAUCUGCUUCACCAAGGAGCUACACUCCCACUUCUUCAGCUUGGGCAAGUGUGUGCCUGUGUGCCGAGGAGCAGAAUUUUUCCAAGCAGAGAAUGAGGGGAAAGGUGUUCUAGACACAGGCAGGCACAUGCCAGGUGCUGGAAAAAGAAGAGAGAAAGGAGAUGGCGUCUACCAGAAGGGGAUGGACUUCAUUUUGGAGAAGCUCAACCAUGGGGACUGGGUGCAUAUCUUCCCAGAAGGGAAAGUGAACAUGAGUUCCGAAUUCCUGCGUUUCAAGUGGGGAAUCGGGCGCCUGAUUGCUGAGUGUCAUCUCAACCCCAUCAUCCUGCCCCUGUGGCAUGUCGGAAUGAAUGACGUCCUUCCUAACAGUCCGCCCUACUUCCCCCGCUUUGGACAGAAAAUCACUGUGCUGAUCGGGAAGCCCUUCAGUGCCCUGCCUGUACUCGAGCGGCUCCGGGCGGAGAACAAGUCGGCUGUGGAGAUGCGGAAAGCCCUGACGGACUUCAUUCAAGAGGAAUUCCAGCAUCUGAAGACUCAGGCAGAGCAGCUCCACAACCACCUCCAGCCUGGGAGAUAGGCCUUGCUUGCUGCCUUCUGGAUUCUUGGCCCGCACAGAGCUGGGGCUGAGGGAUGGACUGAUGCUUUUAGCUCAAACGUGGCUUUUAGACAGAUUUGUUCAUAGACCCUCUCAAGUGCCCUCUCCGAGCUGGUAGGCAUUCCAGCUCCUCCGUGCUUCCUCAGUUACACAAAGGACCUCAGCUGCUUCUCCCACUUGGCCAAGCAGGGAGGAAGAAGCUUAGGCAGGGCUCUCUUUCCUUCUUGCCUUCAGAUGUUCUCUCCCAGGGGCUGGCUUCAGGAGGGAGCAUAGAAGGCAGGUGAGCAACCAGUUGGCUAGGGGAGCAGGGGGCCCACCAGAGCUGUGGAGAGGGGACCCUAAGACUCCUCGGCCUGGCUCCUACCCACCGCCCUUGCCGAACCAGGAGCUGCUCACUACCUCCUCAGGGAUGGCCGUUGGCCACGUCUUCCUUCUGCCUGAGCUUCCCCCCCACCACAGGCCCUUUCCUCAGGCAAGGUCUGGCCUCAGGUGGGCCGCAGGCGGGAAAAGCAGCCCUUGGCCAGAAGUCAAGCCCAGCCACGUGGAGCCUAGAGUGAGGGCCUGAGGUCUGGCUGCUUGCCCCCAUGCUGGCGCCAACAACUUCUCCAUCCUUUCUGCCUCUCAACAUCACUUGAAUCCUAGGGCCUGGGUUUUCAUGUUUUUGAAACAGAACCAUAAAGCAUAUGUGUUGGCUUGUUGUAAAA